AGAGCUGGGCGGUGGCGGGCGCUGCUGAAGGAGUCUCGCUGAGCUCGAGGAGGUGGCGCGAUGGAGGGACUGGAAGAGAAUGGAGGUGUUGUCCAAGUUGGAGAAUUGUUACCUUGCAAGAUUUGUGGAAGAACAUUCUUUCCAGUAGCAUUAAAAAAACAUGGACCCAUUUGCCAGAAGACUGCAACUAAAAAACGGAAGACUUUUGAUUCAAGCAGACAGAGAGCUGAAGGAACUGAUAUUCCAACAGUAAAACCUCUCAAACCGAGGCCAGAACCACCAAAGAAACCAUCUAAUUGGAGAAGGAAACAUGAAGAAUUCAUUGCUACCAUAAGAGCAGCUAAAGGCCUUGAUCAGGCCCUCAAAGAGGGUGGCAAACUUCCUCCUCCUCCUCCACCUUCUUAUGAUCCUGAUUAUAUUCAAUGUCCAUAUUGUCAGAGGAGAUUCAAUGAAAAUGCAGCUGAUAGACAUAUAAAUUUCUGUAAAGAACAGGCAGCACGUAUUAGUAAUAAAGGGAAAUUUUCUACAGAUACCAAAGGAAAACCAACUUCUCGGACACAGGUGUAUAAGCCACCCGCACUUAAAAAGUCAAAUUCUCCUGGAACUGCAUCAUCAGGAUCUUCACGAUUACCGCAGCCAAGUGGCGCUGGCAAAACUGUUGUAGGUGUUCCUUCAGGUAAAGUGUCUUCAAGUAGCAGCUCUUUGGGAAACAAACUUCAGACCUUAUCUCCCUCUCAUAAAGGGAUAGCAGCCCCUCAUGCAGGCUGUCUCAGCCUCAGCCUGAUUCUGAGGAGAUUCUCAGCCUGAUUCCUGUUGGAGAGGUGAUGCGGUCACUUGGAGGAAAAGAGGGCACUCUGGCUUUUUAAGUUUUCAGCAUACUUGUGCUGAUUCUUUCUCAUCUUUGUGAGCUUACCUAACUUCAGUCUUUGAGGCUGCUUACCUUUGGAUGGGUUUGUUUUUUUGAACAACUCUGGCUACUUUUCCAUAGGGCUGCUUGUGUAUGCUGGGUGUCCACUCCAGUCACUAGUCACCUUGGAUUUUUCAGUAGCUGGAGGUGUCACCAGUGAAGGCUACAAAUCAGCAAAGGUAGUGGCCUGCCCCUCCUCCUGGGAGCUUCAUUUUAGGGAUGCCUCAAACCUCUGUCAGCCAAAGAACACCUGUGGGUGUGGCUGAAGACUCCAGUUGGGAGGCUCCACCUGGUGAUGAGGAAUGGGACUGGGAACCUGCUUAAUAAAGCAGUCUGGCCACAUUUUUAUGGGACCACUGUGGUGUGCUGUUGUACCACUUCCACCUCUGGGUCGGCAUGGGCUCUCCAAACCCCAGAGACUGAAACUGCUAAGUUGCCCAAACAGCAAAGAUGAUGGCCUGCACACCCUGUGGGAGUUCUAUCCCAGGGACUUUGCAAAUCUCUGUAGGCCAGAGAACACCUGCAGGGCUGGCUGGAGGUCCCAGUUGGGAGGUUCUUUCCAGUGAGGAGGGGCAAUAUUGGGGACUUACUUAAAGAAGCAGUGUGGCCACACUUUCCUAGAGCAGCUGUGUUGUGCUGGGUUACCACUUUCGUCCCAGUUGGCUUUGGCUCUCUGUGGGCCAGAGAAUACCAGCAGGGAUGGUUGGAGGUCCCAGUUGUGAGGUCCUGCUCUGUGAUGAGGAAUGGAUUGGGAACCUGCUUAACCAGCAGUCUGACCACAUUUUGGUAAAGAAGUCAUGCUAUGCUGGGGAAUCCUCUCUGCCUCUGGUUGGUUUGUACUCUCCAAAGCCUGCAGAACAGCUGAGUCACCCAAACAGCAAAGAUGGCAGCCUGUCCCUUCCCCUGGGAGUUCCAUCCCAGGUAGGCUCAAAACUGCUACUGGUGGCUGGCUGGAAUUCCAAGCCAGUGGGUCUUAUCCUGUGAGGUGUUAUGAAAGUGAGACCUGCAGACUGUCUCUACUUGGUCCUCUUGAUUCAGCCUUUUUUCCUAAGGGUAUGUACGGGGGUCUAACAUCCUGCUUUGCUGGAGUUGCAGUUACUUUUGCUGGGAAGUUUGGAGUUCCUGGGUCUUUGCCUGUGCCGGAGCAGCUGCUCUGCCAAGACUCCCCAUAUCUGUAUGUCAGACUGAAGGCUCUAGUGGAGUGGCUUCACAAGGGCGUCUCUUGACCCAAGGGUUGCAAAGAUCCGUUGGAGAAGCGUGGUUUCCCAGGGUCACACGUUCACUCACUGCUUCCCUGGGCCAGAGAGGUUCACCUUGCUCUGUGUCGCUCCAAGGUGGGCUGUCAUCCUGCCUCUCUUUUCUUUGUUCUCUGUGGGUCAAGUUGUUUCCUUGAUUAGUCCCAAUGCAAGUACAUGGAUGUUUCAGAUGAAGGUGCUGUAUUUACUCACCCCUUUUCCUGUUAUUUUCAAGUGUAAGUUAUAUGUGGCUCACAUUCAUUUUGGUUUUUAUGUGGGAAAUAUAUACAAAGAUAUCUGUCAAAUGAUAGUAACUACAUUUUGCUUCUCAAUUCAGACUACAUAGAAAAUGGAAGACCUAAAGGAAUAUAAUGUAAUUAUCAUUAUAGAAAAGGAAAAAAAAAUCAACCAACAAUAUCUUUUGAGUUAAGUGAUUUUUCUUAUUGUUGUGCUUCCAAAAACAAGAGACAGGCUAUCCAUAAGAAAGAGACAGUUUAUCAGUAGAUCAGGUAGUUGAAAAGUAAAAAAAUUUUAUCUUUUAGUGGUAAGAAACUGAUCUGAUUUAUUUUCUUCUCCAAUGAGUUGACUCAUUGGAUGAUUAAGUGAAGUAUAGACAUAGCAAUAUGUGCUUUAAUUUUACAAAGUCAUUUUACCAUAUCACAGAGAAUUGGCCUCCAUGUUAGGUAACAAUAUUUGUUCAUAGUGUUGUUUAUAGUUUCACUUACAGUUGAUCAUAGAUUAAAAGCUGAUAUUUUUCAGUAUUUCUAUAGUACUGGCAAUUUUAUCAGUUGGCAAUAUUAAAUUGUACUGACACAGUAUUCCUAGAUAGGACGUGUAAAGCUGGCUGGUGUAAUGAAGAGAGGCGCUGACCUUGGAGUUAGAAGACUAGGUUUCUGCAUCAUAAUCUGCCACUAAAUAGCUUUGGGCAUGUAUCUCUUUGUCAUGCUGUGACAUAUUGUCUGACUGUGACAACAUCUGUGACUCUGGUUAGACCUUGACAACUGAUCCAAGAAAAUCUGACCAACAUACCUGGUUACUAAUGGAAAAUAUGCUUUUGCUAACAAGCAGAGAUUUUGAGUACAAUAAUUUUGUCAGUUGUGCAUUGCUUAUGAUGAAUGCCAUGAAGAAUACAUAUUUUUUGGCUAUCCCACAUCAUAUAUAACUGUCAAUCAUACCUGUUCAAAUUCUGAUUGUCCAUUCUGUAUAAGAUCCUUGCAGAUUAAAGGAAGCUUUCCAACUACUGGAAAGAGAGCUGUGGAGCUCAUUUCUACCAAUAUAUUACUAUAUUAACUGGAACAUUGUGUUACUGUAUUAAAUUAGAACCAUUCAUAGCUGUCUAUUUAGUGACAGAGUUCCUUCCUUUUUUUUUCUUUUUUUUUUUUUAAGAAUUAGUGAAGUAAUGAUUUGUUUCUCUUGCUAGAUUGUAAGCUCCAUGAUGGCAAAGACUAUGUCUGCCUUGCUUCCAUUUGUAACUAAAAUCUAGCAGAAUGCCUAGGCUAACAAAAAAUUUUUGGUUAAGUGAAAAAAGAUAAUAAAUUAAUUCCCUCAUCUGUUAAUCUAUUGGCAUGUCACAGAAUUAUCAUCUGGUACCAGUGAAAGAAUUACUUAAAGUUUGUAUGACAACUGUUAUUUCGAUUUAUACAGAUGAUUCAGGAUUGAGUAAAGGUUGAAUUAAGACAUUUGGUCAGGUGUAAUGCUCAAUAAAUUGAGCAUUCGCUGAGAUUAGUAAAUGCUGUUAUUUCAGUGGAUUGCAAUUAUUUAAAGUCUGGUGUAUGUAAUCUUUAUUGUAGUCCACUUUAAUCAGGCAUACCAGUGAUCUGUAAUAGAAUCAUGCCACAAAGAGAUUUAUUUUUACACUCAGAAAAAUUCUCAUAUGUUUGGUUGUUUGCUUCUAGACAGUUUGUGGAUUAGGCCAGGUGCAGUGCCUCACACCUGUAAUCCCAACACUUUGGGAGAGUGAGGUGGGAGAGUCGCUUGAACCCAGGAGUUUGAGACUUGCCUGGGCAACAUAGUAAGAACUCGUCUCCAUUAAAAAAACAAAAACAAAAACAACCUUUUUAAACCUUUUUUUAAAUGUAAAAAAAAGCAAUCAAAUCAAUUUCUAGGUCAAUUUUAACAGAUUUGUUUAAAAAACAACAAAACACACCCAAGUAGAAAGUUUUUCCCUUCUUCUAAAAGAUGAUUAUCUUUUUUUUUUCUUUUUUUUUUUUUUGAGAUGGAGUUUUGCUCUUGUUGCCCAGGCUGGAGUGCAAUGGUGCGAUCUUGGCUCACCGUAACCUCCGCCUCCUGGAUUCAAGUGAUUCUGCUGCCUCAGCCUCCCCAUUAGCUGGGACAGGUGUGUGCUACCAUGUCUGGCUAAUUUUGAAUUUUUAUGGGUUUUCACCAUGUUAGGCUGGUCUCAAACUUCCGACCUCAAGUGAUCCAUCCACCUCGGUUUCCCAAAUUGCUGGGAUUACAGGCAUGAGCCACCACGCCCGGCCAAAAGAUGAUUAUCUUUAAUACCAGGAAAUUUUAGAAAUACAGUGAAACACAGAUCUUUUAAAUAAAUAUUUCCCCAUUUGAAUUGUUCCCUAGAGUUUACACAGUUGUACCUUAUUACCAGUUUAAAUGGAUAUCUCAGUUAAUAAUUUUCAAUAGUGAAACUAUCAAAUAUCAGAGAUUUACUUCCUUUUAGUUACUAUGAAAAGCACAUUUACUUUGGAGAGCAACUGUAAUACACCUAAAAUUAGAGCAACCAAAGGCAUGUAUGGAGCAUUUUUUAAUUUAAAAAAUUGCAUUUUGUUUCUCAUACCUUAUUUAAAACAUUAAGAAGUAAAUGUCUUUAGUUUUUGAGUACAUUUUUAUAUGAAUAGGAAACAUGCUGUUUUCAUAAUCCAGUCUUUUGAUGUGUGUGAAAUGAAUUUGUGUGGAGCGUUAUGUGAAUUUUUAUGAACUUAUCUUUUAUUGUUGAUCUAGAAAUGCUUGUGAUAACCUAGAAUUCCAGACCUCGGUUUCUUAUGUGGAUAACAAUGAUUGGAGAUUUUGGAUAGGGAGCUAACUUUGCUGUGGAAUUGAGAUACUAAUUAUUUGUGUAGGAUUGAUAAAUUUAGGAUCAAAAGUAGAGGUAUGACACAUUUCAAAACUGCCUUAGAGCAGGGGGGUGUUCAAUCUUUUGGCUUCCCUGGGCCACACUGAAAGAAGAAUUGUCUUGGACCACAUAUAAAAUACACGAACGCUAAUGAUAGCUGAUGAACUAAAAAAAAAAAAAAAAAUUUCAUAAUGUUUUAAGAAAGUUUACGAAUUUGUAUAGGGCCCCAUUCAAAGCCAUCUUGGGUGGCAUGUGGCCUGUGAGCUGCUGGUUGGACAAGAUUGCCUUAUAGCAUCAUAACAACAGAGGUGUGCAAAGAUACAAAAUACCAUCCGGUAAAUUCUUUUCCCAAUAUUAUUUCAGAAAUCAUCUUUUUGUUAUAUCUCAAUCUACAGUACUUGCUACACUCCUACAAGGUACCUAGUAAGCCACACUAAAAUUACUUAUUUCGUAAGUGAAUUCACUCUCCUGGUAUCAACAGUAAAUGACUUUUCCUAUGUUAAAGUUUAUUUCAAAUCAGGGAUAGGUUGAUAUCGUCACCAUACUCAUUCAGCUAUGAGUAUUUUGAAGGCCUGUGAAAGUAUUAUAUGUAUAAAAUCUUGAUUGUUAUUGAGAUUUAUAGAUUUUGUUUUUGAUAGCCUAAUGGCAACUUAGAAUGUAAGUUAUUAAGUGAUUAUAGCCUAAAAAUAGCAUUCAUUAACUUUUAGCCUAAGUAACAUUUGAGUUUUGAAUGUACAUAUAUAUAUAUGCACACAUAUAAAUCAAGUUGAAUGUUAUAAUACAAGUAUGGUUAAAAUCAUUACUGGAACCUGUCCUUCAAUUAGGUUUUCAAAAUCUGAAAAUAUUGGCAAUCUUUUUAUAUAUGUAAUGUUUCCAUUGGAUAAUUACCUUUAGGUUUUUAUUAUAUUUUACACAUCUUUCUUGAACUGAACUUUGUUGUAUCACAUGUAGGAUUUGACCAUUUCUUAUCAUAUAAGAGGAAUAUGUUUUUAAAAUAUAGUCAAAAAUUUUCUAAAUUUUAAUUUCAGGAAGUUUUUUCUGAGAAAGAAAAAUUUUAAUCCUUAUUUCCAGAAUCAUGUAAGAUAACCACUGUUUGGAAGAAAAAUGUUUUGAUAAUUAAGGAUUAGAAUAAAAUCUGAAUGUUUAAAAUUCCAA